CUGAAGCCGGAAGCUACCUAUCUGGUAGGGAGCUCCCCCAGCACCGAAGACUGCGAUGGUGAGUGAGGACGCAUGCGCGAGAGGACCCGCCGGGGGUUCAGCGUCUCUGCUCCCCAGUCUGUGUGGUUUCCCCCUGACUUCUGCGCUGACCCAGGGGCUGGAGCGAAUCCCAGACCAGCUCGGCUACCUGGUACUGAGUGAAGGUGCAGUGCUGGCGUCAUCUGGGGACCUGGAGAAUGAUGAGCAGGCAGCCAGUGCCAUCUCUGAGCUGGUCAGCACAGCCUGCGGUUUCCGGCUGCACCGCGGCAUGAAUGUGCCCUUCAAGCGCCUGUCUGGUGUGUCUCUCCUCCAGUGGUCUUUGGAGAACACACACUGCUGGUGACGGUGUCAGGACAGAGGGUGUUUGUGGUGAAGAGGCAGAACCGAGGUCGGGAGCCCAUUGAUGUCUGAGCCUGCCGGAGGGCGAGGGUCGGAGAAGCGGAUUGGGUCCUGGGCCUCUGUGAUGAGGCAGGCACACCUGUCGGUCUUGGCUUGCUGCUAGAACUAGGGCCUUCUGCUCGCCCACCUCCCACCCCUACCUGGACGGGCCCAGGCUUGGGGACUCUGAGCUGUGUUAAGGAGAACAAGGGCAAGGAGACCUCCCUUUGUGCUCCCUCACUCCCUAAUAAACAUGAGUCUGAUGUUCUCCA